AGCUGAAUGGGCGCGAGAGCGGCGCUGGGGGCGGGUGGGGGCGCGGGGUACCGGGCUGGCGGCCGGCCGGCGCCCCCUCAUUAGUAUGCGGACGAAGGCGGCGGGCUGCGCGGAGCGGCGUCCCCUGCAGCCGCGGACCGAGGCAGCGGCGGCACCUGCCGGCCGAGCAAUGCCAAGUGAGUACACCUAUGUGAAACUGAGAAGUGAUUGCUCGAGGCCUUCCCUGCAAUGGUACACCCGAGCUCAAAGCAAGAUGAGAAGGCCCAGCUUGUUAUUAAAAGACAUCCUCAAAUGUACAUUGCUUGUGUUUGGAGUGUGGAUCCUUUAUAUCCUCAAGUUAAAUUAUACUACUGAAGAAUGUGACAUGAAAAAAAUGCAUUAUGUGGACCCUGACCAUGUAAAGCUCCUGAAGGUGCGGCACUCGCCUUGAGGCACUUUCUUCUGAGCUGUGAGCUAUGGGCAAGCAGUGGAGGGGGAAGAGAGCAGCUGAAGCAGAUGCCGGUUCAACUUACUUAAAGAUGUGGGACAAGCUCUGAGGAAGCCCCCAAGACAAUGAUGUCUGGUUGUGCACCAUUGAAGCAAGAACAGAAACCAUCCCAGAGUGGAGGACAUGGCCCAUGUGGUCCUCCUGUUCUGAGUGGCUAUGAGAUGGAGUUCUGUGUGAGCUCUCUACAGAAAAAGCCCUGUCUCCAGGCAAUCAGUGGAGAUCUGUUAAACGAGUUGAAACAAAAGAGGACAAGGAAUUGCUGUGGCUUUAGACGUUGCCAGGACAUGUAGAAACUCACUCAGGAUUUACUACUGCAUCCACUGUCACUUAGGCGCAGGAGGGGUCACAGUCAGAAGGUUGUUUCUUCAAGUUUCUGAGCCAAACUUAACUCUAAAAAGCAAAUAUUCUGUGUUAAAAGACAGUAAUCAACACGGGAGCUACAUCAGACAUCAUAGGACAAAUUGUCAUCUAGAAGAGUAUAUUUUUAAUGCAGGAGAGUUUUUAAAACCCAGAUUGGUGUGAUUUCAUUCCAGAGAGCUCAGAAAUAUGCUCAGCAAGUCUUGCAGAAGGAAUGUCGUCCCAAGUUUGCCAAGACAUCAAUGGCGCUGUUAUUUGAGCACAGGUAUAGCGUGGACUUACUCCCUUUUGUGCAGAAGGCCCCCAAAGACAGUGAAGCUGAGUCCAAGUACGAUCCUCCUUUUGGGUUCCGGAAGUUCUCCAGUAAAGUCCAGACCCUCUUGGAACUCUUGCCAGAGCACGACCUCCCUGAACACUUGAAAGCCAAGACCUGUCGGCGCUGUGUGGUUAUUGGAAGCGGAGGAAUACUGCACGGAUUAGAACUGGGCCACACCCUGAACCAGUUCGAUGUUGUGAUAAGGUUAAACAGUGCACCAGUUGAGGGAUAUUCAGAACAUGUUGGAAAUAAAACUACUAUAAGGAUGACUUAUCCAGAGGGCGCACCACUGUCUGACCUUGAAUAUUAUUCCAAUGACUUAUUUGUUGCUGUUUUAUUUAAGAGUGUUGAUUUCAACUGGCUUCAAGCAAUGGUAAAAAAGGAAACCCUGCCAUUCUGGGUACGACUCUUCUUUUGGAAGCAGGUGGCAGAAAAAAUCCCACUGCAGCCAAAACAUUUCAGGAUUUUGAAUCCAGUUAUCAUCAAAGAGACUGCCUUUGACAUCCUUCAGUACUCAGAGCCUCAGUCAAGGUUCUGGGGCCGAGAUAAGAACGUCCCCACAAUCGGUGUCAUUGCCGUUGUCUUAGCCACACAUCUGUGCGAUGAAGUCAGUUUGGCGGGUUUUGGAUAUGACCUCAAUCAACCCAGAACACCUUUGCACUACUUCGACAGUCAAUGCAUGGCUGCUAUGAACUUUCAGACCAUGCAUAAUGUGACAACGGAAACCAAGUUCCUCUUAAAGCUGGUCAAAGAGGGAGUGGUGAAAGAUCUCAGUGGAGGCAUUGAUCGUGAAUUUUGAACACAGAAAACCUCAGUUGAAAAUGCAACUCUAACUCUGAGAGCUGUUUUUGACAGCCUUCUUGAUGUAUUUCUCCAUCCUGCAGAUACUUUGAAGUGCAGCUCAUGUUUUUAACUUUUAAUUUAAAAACACAAAAAAAAUUUUAGCUCUUCCCACUUUUUUUUUCCUAUUUAUUUGAGGUCAGUGUUUGUUUUUGCACACCAUUUUGUAAAUGAAACUUAAGAAUUGAAUUGGAAAGACUUCUCAAAGAGAAUUGUAUGUAACGAUGUUGUAUUGAUUUUUAAGAAAGUAAUUUAAUUUGUAAAACUUCUGCUCGUUUACACUGCACAUUGAAUACAGGUAACUAAUUGGAAGGAGAGGGGAGGUCACUCUUUUGAUGGUGGCCCUGAACCUCAUUCUGGUUCCCUGCUGCGCUGCUUGGUGUGACCCACGGAGGAUCCACUCCCAGGAUGACGUGCUCCGUAGCUCUGCUGCUGAUACUGGGUCUGCGAUGCAGCGGCGUGAGGCCUGGGCUGGUUGGAGAAGGUCACAACCCUUCUCUGUUGGUCUGCCUUCUGCUGAAAGACUCGAGAACCAACCAGGGAAGCUGUCCUGGAGGUCCCUGGUCGGAGAGGGACAUAGAAUCUGUGACCUCUGACAACUGUGAAGCCACCCUGGGCUACAGAAACCACAGUCUUCCCAGCAAUUAUUACAAUUCUUGAAUUCCUUGGGGAUUUUUUACUGCCCUUUCAAAGCACUUAAGUGUUAGAUCUAACGUGUUCCAGUGUCUGUCUGAGGUGACUUAAAAAAUCAGAACAAAACUUCUAUUAUCCAGAGUCAUGGGAGAGUACACCCUUUCCAGGAAUAAUGUUUUGGGAAACACUGAAAUGAAAUCUUCCCAGUAUUAUAAAUUGUGUAUUUAAAAAAAAGAAACUUUUCUGAAUGCCUACCUGGCGGUGUAUACCAGGCAGUGUGCCAGUUUAAAAAGAUGAAAAAGAAUAAAAACUUUUGAGGAACUCUCGUAGUCUGGUUAAUUUGGGUGCUUAUGUCUAUGAAUCUACCCAAAACCUCCUUCUUGGAUGCUGCUGCUAGGCGGAGACCUCUCUGUGGAUGCCAGUAGUGAGGGACAGAGAAUUAAGGCACCUGGUCCUGCAAGCUGCUUGAGUCCAGACAACUGUGAACCCUUCUGAAGAGAUGCUGGGUGUCGGUGGCUUCCUCCCCAAAGACAGGCUGCCCCUAGCUUCUGUCUCUUAAUGGCUCUAGCCUCUGAUAUCAGAAGAUCUGCUACUCUGUUCCCAGCCUGCCCCAGACUCGGCUGCCGCCAUCGCUGUUCUCCACUCUGUGGCUGCUCUUGUCACUAAUGCUACCUGCCUCCACUUUCCCUUCCUGCAACUGCUUGUGCAGCCCCAGUGCAGCCUUGGCCCCAGCCCAUUCGAACGUCUUCCCAUCUCCCUCCUCCUCACCAUAUGCAGGGCCAGGAGUCAGGUCAUAGCAUUCAAAGCAGAGUCCCUUCUGUCUCCUGGGGUCUGGGAUCCAGCUCAGAGUGGCCAGGAGAGCAAAAGUCAUAUUUCUCUCGUUUUGUGUCUUUACAGAUAAUUUUGUAUGAAUUUUAUUUCCUACUCUAUAAGCUACUGCUUGUUUAAGAGAAAAUGUUUUAAGAUUAUCACCCAUCAAAUGAGUUUAGAAAAUUGAGACUCUGGAAGAUGGUCCACAGCUCCCUUGUGGCUCAGGUGGUGCUGGGCUUACACCACACAGCUCCACCCCUACAUCCCUCAGGGGGUUAUUGGAGAAGCCGGAACUUCCUCAGACAACGUUCUUAAUGCUACGAGCGCCUCCUUGCUGGUAUGAGGAGACUUGCCUACCUGCUUCUCAAGGCUGCUGGGAUGUGUGGUGCUCAAAGCUUCCACUUGGUCAGCUUGCAGCCAUUCUCAGGCCUGCUCCCAUCCCCAUCCCUCCUCCCUGUAAGGCCCUUCUUGCAUCCUUAGGUUGCUUUGCUCAUGUCUCUCAACUUUUACUUACUCAGGUGGUAAGCAGAUACCCUAAAAAGGUAUAUUUUUGUAGACCUUUUAUAGAGUCCACCAGCCAAUAGGAGUUGGCUGGAGAUCAUUCUCAAGAACUUUUCACACUUUGGCAUUCAUUUGUUGGAAGUUGCAUCUUCACUUCAGAGCUGUGCCCCCAUUACUCCCCCACCCCACACACACUCUUCUGAAAACAGACCUUUGCUAGGUGCCUCUGGGUGUUCUAAAGUUGAUCUCCAGUAACUGAGAAUUCACUGCCACACUAACAGCUUUGUAUUGCAUUCUAGACCCGCACACACACCCUCCGACAUAAAUGAAAUCACUGGUUCUGAGGCAACUUAGGAAGACUUACACAUGUUCUGUAUUUUAACAUGCUUCUAGAACUUUGAGCUGCAGAAAAUUUCAGUUUUAGGGUUUUUUAAUUUUAAUUUUUGAUUGAUACAUAGUGAUGUGCAUAUUUUGAGGGUCCAUGUGAUAAUGUAAUACAUUUGUGUAAUUAUAAGGAGCAAAUCUGUGUAACUGGGAUAUCUGUCACAUUAAAUAUUUGUCUUUAUGGUAGAAACAUUUGAAUUAUUCUAGUGAUUUUGAAAUACACAGUAAAUUAUUGUAAACUAUAGGCAUUCUACUGACCUAUCAAACACUAGGUCUUGUUUCUUUUAUCAAACUGUAUGUUUGUACCCAUUAAUCAACCUCUCUUCAUUUCCCCCUACCCUUCUUGGCCUCUGGUAACUACCAAUCUACUCUCUAUCUUCAUGAGAUCCACUUUUUUAGCUCCUACAUAGGAAUGAGAACAUGUGAUAUUUGUCUUUCUGUGUUUGGCUUAUUUCACUUAACAUCACCUCCAGUUCCAUCCAUCUUGCUGCAGAUAACAUGAUUUCAACCUUUUUAUGGCAGAAUAAUAUUCCAUUGUGUAUAUAUACCACAUUUUCUUUAUUCAUUCACCCAUUGAUGGACACUUAGGUUGAUUUCAUGUUUUGGCUAUGUGAAUAGCGCUGCAAUAAAUAUGGGAGUAUAGAUAUAUCUUCAA